AUAUUUAGAUUCCUGAAGCUUCUGCACAUGUAGUUCCUAGAGCUGCUGCUUAUUAAAAUGUCAACAUCUUCAUCUUCUAGCUGGGACAACCUCUUAGAGUCUCUCUCUCUCAGCACAGUAUGGAAUUGGAUACAAGCAAGUUUUUUGGGAGAGACUAGUGCACCUCAGCAAACAAGUUUGGGACUAUUAGAUAAUCUUGCUCCAGCUGUGCAAAUCAUCUUGAGGAUUUCUUUCUUGAUUUUAUUGGGAAUAGGAAUAUAUGCCUUAUGGAAACGAAGUAUUCAGUCAAUUCAGAAAACAUUGUUGUUUGUAAUCACACUCUACAAACUUUACAAGAAGGGCUCACAUAUUUUUGAGGCUUUGCUAGCCAACCCAGAAGGAAGUGGUCUCCGAAUUCAAGACAAUAAUAAUCUUUUCCUGUCCUUGGGUCUGCAAGAGAAAAUUUUGAAAAAACUUAAGACAGUGGAAAACAAAAUGAAGAACCUAGAAGGGAUAAUCGUUGCUCAAAAACCUGCCACGAAGAGGGAUUGCUCCUCUGAGCCCUACUGCAGCUGCUCUGACUGCCAGAGUCCCUUGUCCACAUCAGGGUUUACUUCCCCCAUUUGAAAUGUGAUGGACUCCAAUCUUUUCCAGGAAAGCACUGUUUCCCUCAUGUGUGCAGUGGUGUAUCAAUAAAGAUAGAGAACGCUAUUGAAA